AGAGAUCUCCAGUCAGAAACAGACUGCCUGCGAGGGAGACUCCUGGCUGCUGCUGGGUAGACCAAGGAAACCCAAGACCUUCCGGGAAGACUAAGCAGCCCGGCCUCCGACCCACAGACCUGAGAGCUGGUAAGUGUGGGGUUGGGUUGGCAGGGGUUAAGUGUGUGGGAGAGUCCUGCGCAUGGAUCUCAACUCACAGGCUCUCUGAAUCCUGUCCACAGCACCACUGCCCUUGUUUUCUGACGCCAGUACUGCCUGCAGCAGGCCAGGCUCAGCCUCAGAGAGGAGAGAGCACAAGGCCCCACAACAUGGCGCGCACCAAGCAGACCGCCCGCAAAGCCACCGCCUGGCAGGCCCCCAGGAAGCCCCUGGCCACCAAAGCCGCCAGAAAAAGGGCGUCGCCUACAGGAGGGAUCAAGAAGCCUCACCGCUACAAGCCUGGCACCCUGGCGCUGCGGGAAAUCAGAAAGUACCAGAAGUCCACGCAGCUGCUCCUGCGCAAGCUGCCCUUCCAGCGUCUGGUGCGUGAGAUCGCCCAGGCCAUCAGCCCGGACCUGCGCUUCCAGAGCGCGGCCAUUGGCGCCCUGCAGGAGGCCAGCGAGGCCUACCUGGUGCAACUCUUUGAAGACACCAACCUGUGUGCCAUCCAUGCCAGGCGCGUCACAAUUAUGCCCCGAGACAUGCAGCUGGCCCGCCGCCUCCGUGGAGAGGGUGCCGGAGAGCCCACGCUCCUGGGAAACCUUGCACUCUAGAGGACUUCUUUUCUGUUUGCUUGUGUUUUCUUUUUUCUCUUCCCCCGUAACUGGUAGUUCUGAUGUGAGAAGUUUUGUUCUGUUUUGGUUUCUUUUCCCUCCGGGGGUCCAAAGGUAGCUAAGCAUAAGAUUGCCAGUGGAAACGCAGGCAGAAAUCAGGUGGCAGUUGUGUUUGUGUGUGCUUGUUAGUAAACGUCUCAUCUACUUUGAGGCUCCCAAGGUACUAGUGUCAAGUGGAAAUGUCUCUGUGAGCGAGUUUCAGUUCAACUCUAUAAAAUUAUAAAGAAAUCUUAUUUUUUUUUCUUUACUAUGUCUGCAUACGGGUUCUGUAAACAAAAUAAAUUUCUUAUUAAUCUGA